GUGAGUUGUUAGCUAUUUAGUUCCUUGGUUAGCAGAUUACUUAGGGGAUCUGGUUGGCUGUCAGUUUCUUGCUUUGUAGGCUGGCUUUCUUGGGCCCCUCUUCUUAGUCUGUACCCUCUCCUUGAGCUCUCUCAUCUAUGCCCAUGGCUCAGAUGACAAUCUGUGAUUUGCUGUCCUCCAAAUGUGUCUGUAAGUGAGACCACAUGACCAGCUGCCUCCUCACUGGCCAUCCCACCCAAGUGUCUAGCGGGCUCCUCACACUCAACAUGUCCAGAAAGGGCCUCCUUGUCCAUUCUCCCACAGCUUCUCUGCUGUGCCCCACGCUAGUCAUUCCGCUGCCCUAGCCAGGACCUGAGGGCAUCGCUGAGCUGCCCCGCUCCCUUCCCUCUCUAACCGAACACCAAGCCUGUCAGCUUGACUGUGCUCUUGUGGCCAUUGGCACUGCCAUCUCUGUGGCUCAGGCUGCCACCACUUCUCCACCCAUCUGUGGAGAAGCUGAUGCUCACCCUGCCUCCACUCCACUUCCUCCAUCCUGGCCUCCGCAGGGGAGGCAGCUCUCCUGCUGAAAUCCUCCACUUGGCCCAUGGCCCUCUGGUAGAGUUCAGACUCCCUAAUGUGGGCCAUGAGGCCUUCUGCCACCUGGCUCUGGCCCCUCUCUGCCCAUCUCAUGCCACCUCCACUCCUCCGUGGCCAGCCCAUUCCUGCACAUUGGAUACUGCCUUAGUUGCAGGCCUUUGCACAUGUCAGUCCUACGCCCAGAGUGAUCCCUGCCUCCCUGGAGGCUCCUUUACCCUCCAGCCUUCUUUUCUUGACCUAAAUUUCUCUUUCUCUGGGAGCCUCCUACCCCCUCCUCUAGGCCAUUCACUUCCUCCACAUGCCCCACAGUGCCCACUCUUUCAGCUGGGGCAAUGCUCAUCACACUGCAUAGUAAUUGCUCAAUUGAUUGCUUUUCUUCCCACGGGCUGGAUUGUACCAGUGUCCUUUACUGCAGUGACUGAACAUUCUAGGCAUAGUGGAUUCAAGAAAUCUUGAGUUCAUUGGCUGGUCCACCCGUGGCUCCAAAAUGGUCUCCUGGUCCGUGAUAGCAAAGAUCCAGGAAAUAUGGUGCGAGGAAGAUGAGAGGAAGAUGGUGCGAGAGUUCUUGGCCGAGUUCAUGAGCACAUAUGUCAUGAUGGAGUGGCUGACCAGGAUGCUCCAGCUGUGUCUCUUCACCAUCACGGACCAGGAGAACAACCCAGCACUGCCAGGAACACACGCGCUGGUGAUAAGCAUCCUCGUGGUCAUCAUCAGGGUGUCCCAUGGCAUAAACACAGGAUAUGCCAUCAAUCCAUCCCGGGACCCGCCCCCCAGCAUCUUCACCUUCAUUGCUGGCUGGGGCAAACAGGUCUUCAGCGAUGGGGAGAACUGGUGGUGGGUGCCAGUGGUGGCACCACUUCUGGGUGCCUCUCUAGGUGGCAUCAUCUACCUGGUCUUCAUUGGCUCCACCAUCCCACGGGAGCCCCUGAAAUUGGAGGACUCUGUGGCGUAUGAAGACCACGGGAUAACCGUAUUGCCCAAGAUGGGAUCUCAUGAACCCAUGAUCUCUCCCCUCACCCUCAUCUCCGUGAGCCUUGCCAACAGAUCUUCAGUCCACUCUGCCCCACCCUUACAUGAAUCCAUGGCCCUAGAGCACUUCUAAGCAGAGAUUAUUUGUGAUCCCAUCCCUUCCCCAAUAAAGCAAAGCUUGUCCCACA